AGCUGCCAGCCGGGCCGGUCCGUCCUCCAGGGGACCCCGCGCAGUCCAGGUGAGCGGGGCCGCGUCUGCUUCGGUGACACCAGGGUGAGGCCAGGCCUGCAGCUUCUCACGUUCUCACUAUGUCUGCUCCAGACGAAGGGAGACGGGAUCCCCCCAAACCGAAGGGCAAGACCCUGGGCAGCUUCUUUGGGUCCCUGCCUGGCUUCAGCUCUGCCCGGAACCUGGUGGCCAACGCACAUAGCUCGGCGAGAGCCCGGCCGGCCGCUGACCCCACAGGAGCGCCUGCUGCCGAGGCUGCCCAACCACAGGCUCAGGUGGCUGCCCACCCAGAGCAGACGGCCCCAUGGACGGAGAAGGAGCUGCAACCUUCGGAAAAGGCCUGGGGACCCUGGCUGAGUCCAAGCCUAGGACAUGCUGUCAUGGACGAGGCCUGCCUGCAGCCGGGAAAGGGGGUGCGUGAGAAUGGAAGAGGCUGGCGCUGUGAGCUCAUGAGGACUUCAUCCCGGAGAGCCAGGGUGCCACACCACAGCCCGAUGAAUGUCUGGCUGACCGGGGUCGGGCAGAUGGUGUCCGGGGCCAAAGACCUGGUGUGUUCCAAGAUGUCCAGGGCCAAGGAUGCCGUGUCCUCCGGGGUGGCCAGCGUGGUGGACGUGGCUAAGGGAGUGGUCCAGGGAGGCCUGGACACCACUCGGUCUGCACUUACGGGCACCAAGGAGGUGGUGUCCAGCGGGGUCACAGGGGCCAUGGACAUGGCUAAGGGGGCCGUCCAAGGGGGUCUGGACACCUCGAAGGCUGUCCUCACCGGCACCAAGGACACGGUGUCCACUGGGCUCACGGGGGCAGUGAAUGUGGCCAAAGGGACCGUACAGGCCGGUGUGGACACCACCAAGACUGUGCUGACCGGCACCAAAGACACAGUGACUACUGGGGUCAUGGGGGCAGUGAACUUGGCCAAAGGGACUGUCCAGACUGGCGUGGAAACCUCCAAGGCUGUGCUGACCGGCACCAAAGAUGCUGUGUCCACUGGGCUCACAGGGGCAGUGAAUGUGGCCAGAGGAAGCAUUCAGACCGGUGUGGACACCAGUAAGACUGUCCUAACAGGUACCAAGGACACCGUCUGUAGUGGGGUGACUGGUGCCAUGAAUGUGGCCAAAGGAACCAUCCAGACCGGCGUGGACACCAGUAAGACUGUCCUAACAGGUACCAAGGACACCGUCUGUAGUGGGGUGACUGGUGCCAUGAAUGUGGCCAAAGGAACCAUCCAGACCGGCGUGGACACCAGUAAGACUGUCCUAACAGGUACCAAGGACACCGUCUGUAGUGGGGUGACUGGUGCCAUGAAUGUGGCCAAAGGAACCAUCCAGACCGGCGUGGACACCACCAAGACUGUCCUAACUGGCACCAAGAACACUGUCUGCAGUGGGGUGACCGGUGCCGUGAACUUGGCCAAAGAGGCCAUCCAGGGGGGCCUGGAUACCACCAAGUCUAUGGUCAUGGGUACGAAAGACACGAUGUCCACUGGGCUCACAGGGGCAGCGAAUGUGGCCAAGGGGGCCAUGCAAACUGGGCUGAACACAACCCAAAAUAUCGCAACAGGUACAAAGGACACCGUCUGCAGUGGGGUGACUGGUGCCAUGAAUUUGGCCAGAGGAACCAUCCAGACAGGCGUGGACACCACCAAGAUCGUUCUAACUGGUACCAAGGACACUGUCUGCAGUGGGGUCACCGGUGCUGCGAAUGUGGCCAAAGGGGCCGUCCAGGGCGGCCUGGACACUACAAAGUCUGUCCUGACUGGCACUAAAGAUGCUGUGUCCACUGGGCUCACAGGGGCUGUGAACGUGGCCAAAGGGACCGUCCAGACCGGCGUAGACACCACCAAGACUGUCCUAACCGGCACCAAGGACACCGUCUGCAGUGGGGUGACCAGUGCUGUGAACGUGGCCAAAGGGGCCGUCCAGGGGGGCCUGGACACCACCAAGUCUGUGGUCAUAGGUACAAAAGACACGAUGUCCACUGGGCUCACGGGGGCAGCGAAUGUGGCCAAGGGGGCUGUCCAGACAGGUGUAGACACAGCCAAGACCGUGCUGACCGGCACCAAGGACACAGUGACUACUGGGCUCGUGGGGGCAGUGAAUGUCGCCAAAGGGACCGUCCAGACAGGCAUGGACACCACCAAAACUGUCCUAACCGGUACCAAGGACACCAUCUACAGUGGGGUCACCAGUGCCGUGAACGUGGCCAAGGGGGCUGUGCAAACUGGGCUGAAAACGACCCAAAAUAUCGCGACAGGUACAAAGAACACCUUUGGCAGUGGGGUGACCAGUGCUGUGAAUGUGGCCAAAGGGGCUGCCCAGACAGGUGUAGACACGGCCAAGACCGUGCUGACCGGCACCAAGGACACAGUCACUACUGGGCUCAUGGGGGCAGUGAAUGUCGCCAAAGGGACUGUCCAGACCAGUGUGGACACCACCAAGACUGUCCUAACUGGUACCAAGGACACCGUCUGCAGUGGGGUGACCGGUGCUGCGAAUGUGGCCAAAGGGGCCAUCCAAGGGGGCCUGGACACUACAAAGUCUGUCCUGACUGGCACUAAAGAUGCUGUGUCCACUGGGCUCACAGGGGCUGUGAAGUUGGCCAAAGGGACUGUCCAGACCGGCAUGGACACCACCAAGACUGUGUUAACUGGUACCAAGGAUGCUGUGUGCAGUGGGGUGACCGGUGCUGCGAAUGUGGCCAAGGGGGCCGUCCAGAUGGGUGUAGACACGGCCAAGACCGUGCUGACCGGUACCAAGGACACUGUCUGCAGUGGGGUCACCGGUGCUGCGAACGUGGCCAAGGGUGCUGUGCAAACUGGGCUGAAAACGACCCAAAAUAUCGCAACAGGUACAAAGAACACCCUUGGCAGUGGGGUGACCGGUGCUGCGAAAGUGGCCAAAGGGGCCGUCCAGGGGGGCCUGGACACUACAAAGUCUGUCCUGACUGGCACUAAAGAUGCCGUGUCCACUGGGCUCACAGGGGCUGUGAACUUGGCCAAAGGGACUGUCCAGACCGGCGUGGACACCAGCAAGACUGUCCUGACCGGUACCAAGGACACCGUCUGCAGUGGAGUCACUGGUGCCGUAAAUGUGGCCAAAGGGACCGUCCAGACAGGUGUGGACACAGCCAAGACGGUGCUGAGUGGCGCUAAGGAUGCAGUGACUACUGGAGUCACGGGGGCAGUGAAUGUGGCCAAAGGAACCGUGCAGACCGGCGUGGACGCCUCCAAGGCUGUGCUUAUGGGUACCAAGGACACUGUCUUCAGUGGGGUUACCGGUGCCAUGAGCAUGGCCAAAGGGGCCGUCCAGGGGGGCCUGGACACCACCAAGACAGUGCUGACCGGAACCAAAGACGCAGUGUCCGCUGGGCUCAUGGGGUCAGGGAACGUGGCGACAGGGGCCACCCACACUGGCCUCAGCACCUUCCAGAACUGGUUACCUAGUACCCCCGCCACCUCCUGGGGUGGACUCACCAGUUCCAGGACCACAGACAAUGGUGGGGAGCAGACUGCCCUGAGCCCCCAAGAGGCCCCGUUCUCUGGCAUCUCCACGCCCCCGGAUGUGCUCAGUGUAGGCCCGGAGCCUGCCUGGGAAGCCGCAGCCACUACCAAGGGCCUUGCGACUGACGUGGCGACGUUCACCCAAGGGGCCGCCCCAGGCAGGGAGGACACGGGGCUUUUGGCCACCACACACGGCCCCGAAGAAGCCCCACGCUUGGCAAUGCUGCAGAAUGAGUUGGAGGGGCUGGGGGACAUCUUCCACCCCAUGAAUGCGGAGGAGCAAGCUCAGCUGGCUGCCUCCCAGCCUGGGCCAAAGGUGCUGUCGGCGGAACAGGGGAGCUACUUCGUUCGUUUAGGUGACCUGGGUCCCAGCUUCCGCCAGCGGGCAUUUGAACACGCGGUGAGCCACCUGCAGCACGGCCAGUUCCAAGCCAGGGACACUCUGGCCCAGCUCCAGGACUGCUUCAGGCUGAUUGAAAAGGCCCAGCAGGCUCCAGAAGGGCAGCCACGUCUGGACCAGGGCUCAGGUGCCAGUGCGGAGGACGCUGCUGUCCAGGAGGAGCGGGAUGCCGGGGUUCUGUCCAGGGUCUGCGGCCUUCUCCGGCAGCUGCACACGGCCUACAGUGGCCUGGUCUCCAGCCUCCAGGGCCUGCCCGCCGAGCUCCAGCAGCCAGUGGGGCGGGCGCGGCACAGCCUCUGUGAGCUCUAUGGCAUCGUGGCCUCAGCUGGCUCUGUAGAGGAGCUGCCCGCAGAGCGGCUGGUGCAGAGCCGCGAGGGUGUGCACCAGGCUUGGCAGGGGUUAGAGCAGCUGCUGGAGGGCCUACAGCACAAUCCCCCGCUCAGCUGGCUGGUAGGGCCCUUCGCCUUGCCCGCUGGCGGGCAGUAGCUGUAGGAGCCUGCAGGCCCGGCGCGGGGUCGCCCUGCUCUGUCCAGGGAGGAGCUGCCUCAGAACUUUCUCCCCGCCCCCAAACCUGGAUCGGUUCCCUAAAGCCCUAGACCUUUGGGGCUGCAGCUGGCUGAGCGCCGAGGGGCUGCGGAGGCAGUGACCUUCUUAACUGAGCCACCCCACGCCCUGCUCCGGGCCUGCCUGCAUCUCCCACCUCCUCCCCAGCGCUGCCUGCCCCUCUCGGAGCCUGGGGUCACUCAGACCACCAGCCAAGAGCCUUCCCUUGAAGUCCCCAAGCAAGCACUGCAAUUAGGAAAGAGAAAAAGCAGCGUGCCCAGCCUGGAAGGGCAUCUGUUUGCCCCGCUAGCAACCCUUUUAUAUCUAGCAGGGCUCUUCCAGUCCUGCAGCACGGGCCCCCAGCUAUCAGCGGUGCAGGCAGUGCUGUGGCAUCCCAGGCUCCGGGCAGCUCCGUUCUCAUGCUGAAAGUGGGUCUCCGGCCUUAGCACACACACCUUGAGGGUCUUAAGAACCACAUUCCCUCAUAGUAGAAAGUACUAGAAAAAGCGACACUGCCAUCAUCAUCCCAAGGCAGGCUGCUACUGCCUUUGCUGACCCCCGGGGUGGCCUCACGGUGGGGACAAAGCUGCCAGGAGCCACAGCAGCCACAGCUGGGGCUUUGCACCAGCCUGGCUUGAGACUGAGCAGUUUGCAGGGGGUGGGGGGUGCAAAAAACAAGCAAACAGGCUGCUGCUGCCUCCAGCUGCCCACCACAGGCCUGCCCCAGGCACCUGGGGCUCUGAGGCCCCUGGGGAGGCUGGGCCCAGCAGCUGCCCCUGGAGAACACAGACAAAGGACUUCCCCGCAGGGAACUGUGCCCUAUGGAGGGAUCAGACAGGGCUGGGAACAGCCACAGAGGCUGCGUGCCUAUGGCACAGCCCUUCCUCCGCCGCACACUCCCCCUGGGUCCUCAGGCCCACCCAAGCGCCGGGCUGCAGAGGAAGCGGGGCUGGGGAGGCUGCAGGCAUCAGAGACACUGGUGGUGGCGGACCCGGCCGCCGGGCCCCGUGCUCUCAGGCUAGCCCAGGUCGUGGAGGCUGGCAGGCUCAGGUCGGGUGUGAGACGUGCCGUGGCUGCGCUCAGUCCAGCGGGGAGGAGCCGUUCAGCCCGGCCUCCCCAGGAAGCCAUAUCCCCACUCACCCGGUAAGAGAACCUUGUCGUCCCCUUUCCAUGCUCUCCUAGGACACGAGCCCAGGAACCCCAGACCCAGGGGGAGGAAGGGUGGAGGGGCCCCAGGGGUCACCGUGUGCACCAGGGGCCGUGAGGGGCCGGGGCAUUCAGCUCAGCUCUGAACCGGGGAAGCUGGCACGGCAAGGACUGCCUCAGGUGACGGGCCGUGAGAGGGGACGGGUCAGGAGCCUUCCCAAGCCUUCUCCUCAGCCCGACACCCAUGGCCAUCGGAGGCUAGGAUGCCAGACACAGCCAUUUGCAGAAAUCAGGCACAGUGACUGCAGCUCACGUCCAGCCAACCAAGCAUGGGGCCGCAGCUCAGGAAGUCCCUUCCCGCCACACCACAGCCUAAUUCUUACUGGGACGGAGGCAACUCGGCUACGCUGGGCAGGACGACAAACACGAGACGCCACUGUGGAAUGAGCAACUUCGGAGCACGGGGUGACUUGCUUGGGACCGUGCCCACGUGACAGCCCCUUAUGCAGAGGAGGAAAGAGAAGCCCCGAGUGGGAGGGGAACCUGUCCAAAGUCACACGGUGUGUGGGUGACACAGCUGGGGUGAGUCGAGGCUGGCCCCUGAGGCCCAUGCUCCCUGAACGCUGGAGACCACUGUCGGCUAGCAGCGGCUCUCAGGGAAGGCCUGGUCUCCACCCUCCCAGCCUAGCCUCGCGGACCCUCGUCCUCCCCACAUCGGACCUGCUCACCUGCCUGGACCCUGGGCUGCCAGAUGCAGGAAGCAUCAAACCCCCCAGCCUCGUGGGUGCGGGGCAGGGCGCAGGCAGCACAGCUUAGAUGCCCUGGUUUGUCCCUCUUGUCUCCUGGGAAGAGCUUGCUCCCGCCCAGCUCUCCUGCCACUGGCCUUUCAGGGUUGGGCUGGGCCCAGAGUGCCUUUUAGUCGCUUCUCACGGUGGCCUGAUGGCUCAACCCAGUCCCAAACGGGCCCAGUGACACUGCCGCCUGCGCCCCAGCUCAGGCCCCCACUGCACCAGCAAUGCUAGAAAACCAAGCCAAUAAAAGUGAUUUCUUUUUUCAUUAAAAAA